GGGUCCCAGGAAGGAAACUCAGCCUGGCUGUCAGAGCUUGCAGCGUAAUCAGUGUGUUUAUUGUAAAUAAAUAGGACAUUGGAAGAAAAAAUGCCCUCAGCUAAAAAGAAAACAAGGUGACUUGGAGCAAGAGGCUCCAGACAAGGAGGAAGGGACCCUGCUCAACCUGGCAGAAGGGUUAUUGGACUGAGGGGGACAGGGCUCAAGGACACCCAAAGAGCCUAUUGUCAGGAUGACAGUUAGGGGUAAAGACAUUGAUUUUCUUGUAGAUACCGGUGCUAAACAUUCAGUAGUAACCGCGCCGGUAGCCCCCUUAUACAAAAAGAUUAUUGACGUCAUCGGAGCCAAAAGGAUUUCAGCAAAGCAAGCUUUCUGCUUGCCCCGGACUUCUACUGUAGGAGGACAUAAAGUGAUUCAUCAGUUUUUGUCCACGCCUGACUGUCCCUUGCCCUUAUUGGGAAGGCACUUGCUUAGCAAACUGAGAGCCACUAUCUCUUUUACAGAGCAUGGCUUUUUGCUGCUAAAGUUACCCAGAACGGGAGUCAUUAUAACCCUUAUGGUCCCCCCAGAGGAGGAAUGGAGAUUUUUCUUAACUGAGUUGGGCCAAGAGAUAAGACCAGCUCUGGCUAAGCAGUGGCCAAGAGUGUGGGCGGAAGACAACCCUCCAGGGUUGGCAGUCAACCAAGCCCCCAUACUUAUAGAAGUUAAGCCUAGGGCCCAGCCGUUUAGGCAAAAACAGGAGCCGGUCCCCAGAGAAGCUCCUGAAGGUAUCCAGGUCCAUCUCAAGCACCUAAGAACUUUUCGAAUUAGAGUUCCUUGUCAGUCUCCAUGGAACACUCCCCUCCUGCCUGUUCCCAAGCCUAGGACCAAGGACUACAGGCCUGUACAGGAUUUGCACUUGGUUAAUCAGGCUACAGUGACUUUACAUCCAGCAGUACCUAACCCGUACACAUUGCUGGGGUUGCUGCCAGCUGAGAACAGCUGCUUCACCUGCUUGGACCUGAAAGAUGCUUUCUUUAGAUUCAGAUUAGCCCCAGAGAGCCAGAAGCUGUUUGCCUUUCAGUGGGAAGAUCCGGAGUCAGGUGUCACUACUCAGUACACUUGGACCCGGCUUCCCCAAGGGUUCAAGAACUCCUCCACCAUCUUCGGGGAGGCAUUGCCUCGAGACCUCCAGAAAUUUCCCACCAGAGACCUAGACUGCGUGUUGCUCCAGUAGGUUGAUGACCUUUUGCUGGGACACCCCACGGCAGUUGGGUGCGCCAAGGGAACAGAUAUUCUACUCCGGCACCUGGAGGACUGUGGGUAUAAGGUGUCCAAGAAAAAAGCUCAGAUCUGCCGACAGCAGAUGAUCGAGUGUGGAUCAAGGACUGGAAAGUAGCCUCUUUGUGCCCACGGUGGAAAGGACCCCAGACUAUCGUCCUGAGCACUCCCACCGCUGUGAAGGUAGAAGGAAUCCCAGCCUGGAUCCAACACAGCCAUAUAAAACCUGCAGGGCCUGAAACCUGGGAGGCAAGACCAAGCCCAGACAACCCUUGCAGAGUGACCCUGAAGAAGACGACAAGCCCUGCUCCAGUCACACCCAGAAGCUGACUGGUCCACGCACGGCCGAAGCCUGAGGAAGCUCAUCAUGAGAUUCAUUUUUCUUAAAUUUUGGACUUAUACAGUAAGGGCUUCAACUGACCUUACUCAAACUGGGGACUGUUCCCAGUGUAUUCAUCAGGUCACCGAAGUAGGACAGCAAAUUAAAACAAUCUUUCUGUUCUAUAGUUAUGAAUGUAUGGGAACAUUAAAAGAAACUUGUUUGUAUAAUGCCACUCAGUACAAGGUAUGUAGCCGAAGAAAUGACCGACCUGAUGUGUGUUAUAACCCAUCUGAGCCCCCUGCAACCGCCGUUUUUGAAAAAAGAAUAAGAACUGGCCUUUUCCUAGGUGAUACAAGUAAAAUAAUAACUAGAACAGAAGAAAAAGAAAUCCCCAAGCAAAUAACUUUAAGAUUUGAUGCUUGUGCAGCCAUUAAUAGUAAACAGCUAGAAAUAGGAUGUGGUUCUCUUAAUUAAGAAAGGAGCUAAAGAGUAGAAAAUAAAUAUGUUUGUCAUGAGUCAGGGGUUUGUGAAAAUUGUGGCUAUUGGACAUGUGUUAUUUAGGCUACUUUAAAAAAGAACAAAAAGGACCCGGUUUAUCUUCAGAAGGGGGAAGCCAACCCCUCCUGUGCUGCCAGUCACUGUAACCCACUAGAACUAAUAAUUACCAUUCCCUAGAUCCCCGUUGGAAAAAGGGAGAACGUGUAACCCUGGGGAUCAAUAGGACAGGGUUAAACCCUCAAGUUGCCAUUUUAAUUAGAGGGGAGGUCCACAAGUGCUCUCCCAAAACCAGUAUUUCAAACCUUUUAUGAGGAGCUGAAUCUGCCAGCACCAGAACUUCCGAAAAAGACAAAAAAUUUGUUUCUCCAAUUAGCAGAAAAUGUAGCUCAUUCCCUUAAUGUUACUUCUUGUUAUGUACGCGGAGGAACCACUGUCGGAGACAGAUGGCCUUGGGAAGCCCGAGAGUUGGUGCCUACUGAUCCAGCUCCUGAUAUAAUUCCAGUUCAGAAGGCCCAAGCUAGCAACUUCUAGGUCCAAAAACCUCAAUUAUUAGACAAUACUGUAUAGCUAGAGAAGGGAAAGACUUUAUCAUCCCUGUAGGAAAGCUUAAUUGUAUAGGACAGAAGUUGUAUAACAGCACAACAAAGACAAUUACUUAGUAGGGCCUAAACCACACUGAAAAGAAUCCAUUUAGUAAAUUUUCUAAAUUACAAACUGCUUUGGCUCAUCCAGAAUCUCAUCAGGACUGGACAGUUCCCUCUGGACUAUACUAGAUAUGUAGGCACAGAGCCUACUUUCAGUUACCUAAUAAAUGGGCAGGCAGUUGUGUUAUUGGCACUAUUAAGCCGUCCUUUUUCUUAUUACCCAUAAAAACAGGUAAGCUGCUAGGUUUCCCUGUCUAUACUUCCCGAGAAAAGAAAGGCAUAGUUAUAGGAAACUGGAAAGAUAAUGAGUGGCCCCCUGAAAGGAUCAUACAGUAUUAUGGGCCUGCCACAUGGGCACAAGAUGGCUCAUGGGGAUACCGAACCCCCAUCUACAUGCUCAAUUGGAUCAUACGGUUGCAGGCUGUCUUAGAAAUAAUUACUAAUGAAACUGGCAGAGCUUUGACUGUUUUAGCUUGGCAAGAAACCCAAAUGAGGAAUGCUAUCUAUCAGAAUAGACUGGCCUUAGACUACUUGUUAGUAGCUGAAGGAGGAGUUUGUGGAAAAUUUAACUUAACCAAUUGCUGCCUACAAAUAAAUGAUCAAGGAUAGGAGGUUAAAAUGAUCAAGGAUAGUCAGGGACAUGACAAAGGUGGCACAUGUGCCUUUACAGAUUUGGCACGAGUUUAACCCUGAGUCUUUAUUUGGAAAAUGGUUUCCAGCUAUAGGAGGAUUUAAACCCCUCAUUGUAGGUGUAUUGCUAGUGAUAGGAGCUUGCUUGCUGCUCCCCCGUGUAUUACCCUCGCUUUUUCAAAUGACAAAAGGUUUUGUUGCUACUUUGAUUCAUCAGAAAACUUCAGCACAGGUGUAUUAUAUAAAUCACUAUCGUUCAAUCUCACAGAGAGACUCAAAAAGUAAAGAUGAGAGCGAGAACUCCCACUAAAAGUGAAAAUUCUCAAAGGAGGGAAAUAUGGUGUGAGACCACCACGUCUCCUGCUGUCCUUCCCAGUUCCUCCCCAACCUCCCUUUUUCCCUAGUUUAUAAGACAGGAAAAAAGGGAGAAAGCAAAAAGCUGGAAAAAACAGAAGUAAAAUAAAUAGCUAGACGCCCUCGGCGCCACCACCUGGCCCCGGUGGUUAAAAUAUCAAUAAUAUUAACCCCUGACCAAAACUACUGGUGUUAUCUGUAAAUCCCAGACAUUGUAUGAGAAAGCACUGUAAAAACUUUUUGUUCUGUUAGCUGAUGUUUGUAGCCCCCAGUCACAUUUCUCACGCUUACUUGAUCUAUUAUGACUUUUUCGGGUAGAUCCCUUAGAGUUGUAAGCCCUUAAAAGGGCUAGGAAUUUCUUUUUCAGGGAGCUCGGCUCUUAAGACACGAGUCUGCUGACUCUCCCGGCCGAAUAAAAAAACCUCUUCCUUCUUUAA